GUAAAAGACUCCCCCGUCUGUGGCGGCGGCUGUUUGAUGGGUCCGGAAAUCUCUUGAAGGUGAAUCCAAGCAAGAUAAACGGUGCGGAGAGGAGGCGCGGGGCUGGGCUCAGAGCGGCGGCGGCGGCGGCUCCACUCCCUCCGCGCCCACCCUCCCACCAUGCGGGGCCGCGGCCCAUGGUGAGCCCCAGCAGCCAGCACCAUCGGCUGGAGACGAAGAAGAAGAAGAAGAGGAGGCGGCGAGCGCGGGGGAAGGCGAAAAAGAAAAAGAAAGAAGGGGAGAGGGCUCCCGGCAGCACCAGGACCGACGCGCGCACCAGCUCCGGAGCCCAGCUCGCGCGCGUCUGUGGGGCCGCCUGACUCCGGGGCCGAGGCGGCGGCGGCGGCAGCGGGCGCGGCGGCCCGGGCUGCGCGCCGGCGCGGGACCAUGGAGCGCGGGAUGCACCUCGGUGCAGCGGCCGCCGGCGAGGACGACCUCUUCCUGCACAAGAGCCUGAGCGCCUCCACCUCCAAGCGCUUGGAAGCGGCUUUCCGCUCCACGCCCCCGGGCAUGGACCUGUCCCUGGCGCCGCCGCCUCGGGAACGCCCGGCGUCCUCCUCCUCGUCGCCCCUGGGCUGCUUCGAGCCGGCUGACCCCGAGGGGGCAGGGCUGCUGUUGCCGCCGCCUGGAGGAGGCGGCGGCGGCAGCGCGGGAAGUGGCGGCGGCGGCGGCGGCGGGGUGGGUGUCCCCGGGCUGCUAGUAGGUUCAGCCGGCGUUGGGGGCGACCCUAGCCUAAGCAGCCUGCCGGCCGGGGCCGCCCUUUGCCUCAAGUACGGCGAAAGCGCGAGCCGGGGCUCGGUGGCCGAGAGCAGCGGCGGCGAGCAGAGCCCCGACGACGACAGCGACGGUCGCUGCGAGCUCGUGCUGCGGGCCGGAGUAGCCGACCCGCGGGCCUCCCCGGGAGCGGGAGGUGGUGGCGCGAAGGCAGCCGAGGGCUGCUCCAAUGCCCACCUCCACGGCGGCGCCAGCGUCCCCCCGGGGGGCCUGGGCGGCGGCGGCGGCGGGGGUAGCAGCAGCGGUAGCAGUGGCGGCGGUGGCGGUAGCGGUAGCGGCAGCGGCGGCAGCAGCAGCAGCAGCAGCAGCAGCAGCAAGAAAUCCAAAGAGCAAAAGGCGCUGCGGCUUAACAUCAAUGCCCGAGAGCGCCGGCGGAUGCACGACCUGAACGACGCGCUGGACGAGCUGCGCGCGGUGAUCCCCUACGCGCACAGCCCCUCGGUGCGAAAGCUCUCCAAGAUCGCCACGCUGCUGCUCGCCAAGAACUACAUCCUCAUGCAGGCGCAGGCCCUGGAGGAGAUGCGGCGCCUAGUCGCCUACCUCAACCAGGGCCAGGCCAUCUCGGCUGCCUCCCUGCCCAGCUCGGCGGCUGCAGCGGCAGCAGCUGCUGCCCUGCACCCGGCGCUCGGCGCCUACGAGCAGGCAGCCGGCUACCCGUUCAGCGCCGGACUGCCCCCGGCUGCCUCCUGCCCGGAGAAGUGCGCCCUGUUUAACAGCGUCUCCUCCAGCCUCUGCAAACAGUGCACGGAGAAGCCUUAAACACACCCCCGAAAAACACAAGACCGACCCAAAAUCUAGAGGAAAGCGAAAAGCUGCUCCCCACCCCCUUUAUUUUGGUCCUCUCGUAGUUGUGAAACACUUGCAGAGCAAACAAAGCAGAGGCAAGAACUGAGGAGAAGUAUCAGAGACAAACGGGACUUUUAGCCUUGACAUCCCCAGAAUCUCGGUCUUUGGGGUGGGGAGGGAGGGAGGAGGGAGGUGGAGUUGGGAUGGAGUAUGGAUGUCUUUUUUUUCUCAGAAAAGUGGCAACUUUGGUGGCAGCCUAGACCGCGAGGAAGUGGAAUCUUCCUUAAAGGUGAAACAUAAGUUGAGAAGUAGUGCUUGGUUAUUAAGCCUGGAGAGUGUUUGAAUGGCAAAAUACUAAUCCUACUAAUAAUUGUGGAUUUGGCUAGUGCUGAGGGGGAGAGGAGGGGUUAGGGGUUGGGUAGCAUGAGAGAUGGAAUAUUCAUUCAGACAAAUCAGAAAGGGCACUUGAAAAUAAAUUUUGAUUCUGAGCCAGGAGAAAAACUUGAAAUGUUGACUUAAGUGAGGGGGAAAUAAAACCCAGAGAGAGAGAGAGAGCGAGAGAGAGAGACAUGUUACUAUGAAAGACUUGUAUUUUUUAUUGUCUCUGAACUUUAAUCCUGUGAAAAUGCUCAAAGUUUUGGCGAGAGUGAUAUAAAAAAACUGACUGUGGCUGAAAGAAUUGCAUUUAAAAAUAUUUAUGUGCACCUUGUUACUUUCUACUCUGCAAUGAUGUAUUAACAAUUCAUGGUAUUUAUUUGUUAUUCUUCAAUGACCCUUCCACAUCAACAGUAUUUAUCAUGUGUUAAAGUCAUGGGUCUUAUGUGCAGAUUUUUUUAAUGCCUCUAAAAUUGUUUUAUAGAUUACUUAUGCUGUGUGCCAAGUGUUUAAAGGUUUAUUUGCCAACAAGUAUGAAGAGAAAUAUUGAUGUAUCUGAGCUGCUUAGGUUUAUGAAAGGUCACCUGGAUAUUUUCAGUUGCAUCAUCCCUGUAUUUAAAUUGAGCUUUAAUAAAUUGCUUCAGUCCAAAAAUUACAGGAAAGGUGUAUUCUUAAUUGAUGAAUGAAUUGAUCUCUUUUUUGAAAGGGGACUCCUUUACAUUCCAAAAGGGAAAAACAUCACAGCAAUAGUUGCUAUACGUAAGAACAUGCUAAGCAAAUAUUUUUCCAGGCUGUGCUGUGCAUUUUUAAAAGGUCUAAUUUAAUUGCUUUUAAUAUAUAUGUACAUAUAUGUUAUUUUAACUGUGGAGAAUUAUUUAAGUUAAAAGACUGGUUUGAUUUGCCUAUGGUGUGAAAUCCUUUGUUAUUUUUCUAAAAAAAUAAAAUUUAAAAAGAAAGAAAACUAAGGAAGAACAAGAAGCUAUUUACCCAAAGUGAGCUUUCAGUUUUAGUUUUGCAUGGCUGUUUGACUGCCUUUCCGCCCUAUGAAAAUCAAGAAAAUCUUUUUUAAAAAUGGAGUCCUGCUAUUUUCCACUCCUUGCAGAUAAUACAAAUUCAGUUUGUCAGGUUGGAUGGUGAGUUGGGAGCUGUGAUGGAUCUGUUGGCGGGUUUUGGAUGUGUAAAGAAUGAUAUAUAUAUUAAAUAGGUCAAUCAGACUAUGACAGCUAUGUACGACCAUUUGUAUGUGUAUCUAUGUCAGAAAGAAUCUUUAUUAAAAUAUUUUGAUCAAA